AGAAGCUUCACUGAGCGGGCACUGGAGGUCGCGAGCACGUUGCUAGUGGGCGCGGCUGGCGGGGCCGGGGGCGGCAGGGGGCUAGCGUCCGGCUGAGCCCGGCGGGUUCCUGCACGCGGACCCACGCUUUGUCGGGCUGCUCUGCUGAGUGACACCGCCGUGGCAUCCGAGGAGCUGUGGUCCAGCCUGCGCGGCGGGAAGCGGCGGCGGCGGCUCCAGCGUCCUAAGAGGUAGCAUGGGCCCAGGCCUCUGUGGGGCAGCGGGAGGGGUCUAGAGGGCACCUUCAACCCUGGGCGUGUGUCCGGGAGCUGACUCGCGGCGCGAACCCGGCAACUGCUCCGCGUGCGCCGCUCUUCGGGCUGUGGCAGUGUACGACUGCCAGACGGGUCGUCCACACUCGCCGACCCCACAGACCCCGGCGGCCGAGAGAGGUCCCCCCGCCCUUCCGGGUCGAGCCAGUGUCCUGGCAAAUCUUGCUUUGGGACUGUUUUUCAGCCUCCUUUGCUGUAACCCUUCACCGUGUUCUCCCCCCUUCUUCCGAAGCCAGUUGAAGAGGGGCCCGGAAGCGCCCGCGUUCGGAAUGGUUUUUAAAAUUAGCAAUUUCUUAUUAGGGACUGGCAGACUGGUCCUUACCGCCGUGUUUGGGAAGCCACAAGAGGCCAUUCUUACCUGUUAGAUUCUGAGAAAAGGGACCGCCUAUACCUCUUCUUGACAAAUACCUAAGGAUGCAUUAGUCUGCGUUGGCUGAACUUGGCAUGGUGUGGUUUGGGGGAGACAACACACUUUUUUUGGCCAUCACCCCAGAUUUCUACUGGGGAGUGAAAGCGCCUACUGUACUGAAACUCGAAAGCUCCAUAGUUGAGGACUUUCAACCUGAGAUCAGGGUCAAAACUACCUGUGGAUAGAUUAUUGAAGCGUGUGCAUAUUAACGUCGUGCGUCAAGUCCCCACCUUCCAAGGUUGUAAAACUGAUCAGAUUUACAAUCCGUCUUGAAUUACUCUUUACCAAAAUUGAUCCAUUUAAAACAGCUUUGAAAAUGUGCUUUACCAGCCUUCCUUCUUGUCAGUAGGCACAGGUAUAUUAAUGAAUAGACCUGGCUUUGGGGAAGGCAGCAUUUGCAGCGUUGUGCUUUCCAAUCUAAUCACUUCUAAAUUGUGGGCAUUAGCCCAUUUGAGGUUACAAACUUUGAACCAAGAAUGAGGCCUAUUUUUCACAAAUAAGGAUGACCCAUCAAUUUCUGAUGACUGCUUGUAUUUGUUAUUAUAUGAAAUGAGAAGCUGAAACCUAUCAACACUCUUCAAAAUGCAAUGGAAUGUACCACGGACUGUAUCUCGACUGGCACGCAGGACAUGCUUGGAACCACAUAAUGCUGGUCUCUUUGGACACUGUCAAAAUGUAAAGGGACCUUUACUUUUAUACAAUGCUGAAUCCAAAGUGGUUUUGGUACAAGGCCCUCAAAAACAAUGGUUGCAUUUAUCUGCUGCCCAGUGUGUUGCAAAGGAAAGGAGGCCAUUGGAUGCUCAUCCACCCCAACCAGGAGUCCUUCGCCAUAAGCAAGGGAAGCAACAUGUUUCAUUCAGGAGGGUUUUUUCAUCCAGUGCCACAGCUCAGGGAACUCCGGAAAAAAAGGAAGAGCCUGAUCCUUUGCAAGACAAAUCUAUUAGUCUUUAUCAACGAUUCAAGAAGACAUUUAGACAGUAUGGAAAAGUUCUGAUUCCAGUGCAUCUAAUAACUUCUGGUGUUUGGUUUGGAACAUUUUAUUAUGCAGCCUUGAAAGGAGUGAAUGUCGUUCCUUUUCUAGAACUCAUUGGGUUACCUGACAGUGUGGUAAGCAUCCUGAAAAACUCCCAGAGUGGAAAUGCCCUCACAGCAUAUGCCUUGUUUAAGAUUGCAACACCUGCUCGGUAUACCGUGACUUUGGGAGGAACAUCUGUCACUGUGAAGUAUCUGCGCAGUCAUGGCUACAUGUCCACGCCGCCACCCGUCAAGGAGUAUCUGCAGGACAGGAUGGAAGAGACAAAGGAGCUUAUCACAGAGAAAAUGGAAGAAACAAAAGAUAGACUCACUGAAAAGUUACAAGAAACCAAAGAAAAAGUUUCCUUUAAGAAAAAAGUGGAAUAAGGUGCCUUAUAUAGCAGUAUAGAAAAUUCCUGCACUUUAACCCUUUGGAAACUAUGGGCAAAGAUACAUGUGUCUGAUUAUUUUUUUGGUUAGUUGCCGAAAUAUACUAGUUCUCUGAGGGUUAAAGAAGUAAAAUACCUUUUUAAAGUUAAAUAUCACUAGAAAAAUCAGUGUUAUUACAAGGGAAGAAAUGAACCCAGUUUAAGAAUUUGCCAUCAGUAGCAGUAUUAAGCAGUGGUUAAUGUCUUAGAAGUCAGACUUCUUUUUCAAGGUCUUCAGAACCACACUUGAUUUCUGUUUUGUUGCAGCUGUAAUUGACACAUACUAGGCAGCUGACUCCUUGAAUAUCCAGUGUGACCCAUAAAAUAGUCUGUUAAUACCGGAUCUUAAUUUUUAUGUUAUUCAUUAAGAUUUUAACUAUAUUCAGUACGUAAUUUGGAGACAAACUAGCAUCAUCAAAACUGCCUGUAAAUAAGGUGUUUAGUCUUUCUAUAAAAACAGAAUAGAGCAGUUACCUACCAGUUAAAAUAUCUUAUAUGAAGAAAAUAGAAUAAAGAUCCAGUCAUAUAUGUAAAUAAGAUGUACUGAUUGUACGUAAAUGAAAAAUGGACCCUUUAAAAAUUAUUUUUACCUGAAGCUUGUCAUAAUUUUUUUAAAGCAAAUAUAUAUAUGGUGAUGGUACUUUUCAAAGUGUGUAUUAGUGGUGAUCACCUCAAACAUAAACCUCUGUUGUGAAUCAUUUGUGUCCUUUUCAACUGUCUUUCAGAGGAAAGGUAAAAAAUCAUUAAACCUUAAAUUCAUUGUUAAAAUCAAAUAUUUGUCAGCAGUAACUCAAGCUCAUGGUUCUCAAGCAGAAAAAGGUUUGGGAGACUAAAAAUGGAGUCAGGUUUUCAUGGAGACUGCUAACUCCUUGGGGUAGACAUGGGCCUUGCCUCAGCAAACCAGUGCAAUUUCCCAAUGUCUUAGUUUCAGAAUUCAUGCUGAUUUCAUUAUGGAGUAAAGUUUUAAAUUGUGGCUGCUGCUUUUUGUCUUACAUUGAAGGGAAAUAUCCUUGUUUGAGCAUUCUACUUGAUUUUUUUUUUUUUUUUUUUUUUUUUUGAGACGGAGCCUCCCUCUCUCUCUCCCAGACUGGAGUGCAAUGGUACAAUCUCGGCUCACUGCAUCCUCUGCCUCCCAGGUUCAAGUGAUCCUCCCGCCUCAGCUUUCCAAGUAGCUGGGAGUAUAAGCGUGUGCCACCACACUCAGCUAAUUUUUGUAUUUUUAGUGGAGGUGGAGUUUCACCAUGUUAGCCAGGCUAGUCUCCAACUCCUGACCUCAGCCUCCCGAGUAGCUGGGACUACAGGCGCCCACCACCACGCCCAGCUAAUUUUUUUGUAUUUUUAGUAGAGAUGGGGUUUCACCAUCUUAACAAAGCUAUCAUUAAAUCAUUUGCUUGUAAUGAAAUUCAGCCGUUGUCAGCUGUGAGCGUUGCGGGGCUGGUGGGGUGUGUUUGAGUAUGUAAGUGUCUAUUUCCUGUGCUCUAACAGUGACUAUUUCAGUUCUAACCCUUCAAUUGCUAAUUGGAUGAGGGAAUGGCCUCUUAGAUUGUCCUUGUUUUGACUUAUCUGCUAAGGCGAGAGAAUGUCUGGGUUUGCCACACAGUCCCGCAGGGACCCCUGCUCUUUGCCAGGAUUUUUAUAUCAAGUACUUAGUUUGGCCAAAUUUAGAGUAUAGUUUAAAGGGGAAAAAAAGUUUGUAUUUGAUGAGUCUAAUUACUAUAUUAGAAUGCUUUUUAAAUGAAUAUGCUGUGAUUGGAAUCUCUUCUUGGGGGCCGGGGAGAGUGCUGAGAGAUGCAGCUGUGUCUCUGCUCUCUGCAGUCUUGGGCAGGCAGCACCGCUGUCUCCUGAUACAGAGGGUUGAAUGCACUGCUUCACAUUGAUGCCACAUUUUCAAAUCUAAACAUGAUUAACAUGUUUUUUAAGUAUUUAUCAAAUAAUUCACAUUUUUGCAGGUUUAAGUGCUGUUUUUUAAGAUAUUAAACAUGUUCCUUGUUUCUUUUUUCUUUUUAACCACUGGAGACUAUGUGAAAAUCUUGUGUUAUAUGGAAUUUUUCUAAAACAAUUUCCUUUUACUUUUCAUGUUGCAUAUUUUCCAGUGGGGAUAAAUUGGAGGUUCUUAUUACUAAUAAUCCUGAAACUAAAAUUUGCUUUUCCUGCAUAGACAUCUUUUGUUAGUCCAUUUGAGUUUUGUUGCCAUCCAGUUUCAUGAUCAUGUUGUGUUAGUCUAAUAGACAAUGAGUUACUGCUUGAAUGAUAUGAAAUUCUCUAGUAAAAAAUGCUCUGAAGAUGUGAGAAGCUCUGUUGUAUUACUUGGCACCAGGAAUGUUACAAAAAUGUUGUUGCUAGCAUAUUGCUAACCUAGUCCUUAAGUUUCAGGGAUUCCUGUAAUAUGUUGAGUUUGGAGUAUUAAUAGCAGGCUAACAGAAUACAGUACCAAUAUGCCAAGUUAAAUAAUUGAGAAUAUAUACAGUAUAGUUUGCUAUGUAUAAUAGACCUCAUUUCAUUUACAGUACACCUCACACUUGGGAUUAAUUCACCUAUAACCUCUGUGAACUGCGAGUGCUCGGCAGAAGCAGCCCUGUGUCUUACAUGUCUACAUUUAUAUUUAUAUUUAUAUUUAUUUUUUUGAGACAGAGUCUCACUCUGUCACCCAGGCUAGAGUGCAGUGGCAUGAUCAUAGCUCACUUGCGUCUUGAACUCCUGGCUCAAGUGAUCCUCCCACCUCAGCCUGCUGAGUAGCUGGGACUACAGGUGCACACCACCAUGCCUGGCUAAAGGCAUGUCUGCAUUUAUGCGAGGUGUGUUGACCGGGUGGGGAGGGAGCUAGGACUGAGAUUCGCCUGUGUAAAAUGCACAAAAAGGGUUUGCUAAGCAAAUUGAUAUUUGAAAUGAAAGAUGGAUUAGGUGAGAGACUUAGUUUAUUCAGGAAUAAGAGCAAAACCAACCACAUCAAAAAAUGUAUUUCACUGAGACAGCCUUUUGUACAUACAGCAGGGUGCUGUUUACAGAUUUCAAGAAAGGAGAAAAAGAAUGCUUAUACUGAGAUUACCUACCUCCCAGUAGUGAAAAUAAUAAAUUUAUCCCUUGAAAUAUAA